AGAGCUUGGGCCUGGGCUCACGAGGAAGGGGCUGCAGUUCUCCAAGGAUUCCCGCCUGCUCCCAGACCCCCGGGAGUCGUAGGAACCCGUUCCUGGACGCUGACGUCGGCUUUCAGGGAUCCCUCGCCGGACGCCGCGGAGGGACAGAGCCUGGGAAGCCGUCGCCCCGCCCCGUCCCCGCCCCCGCGCGCAGCGGGCCCGGGGCGCUGAGACCCGCGUAGAGCAAAGCGCAAGGUCCCAGCGCCCCUUGGAUCCUCGGUGGCAGGGUCCGGGCAAGUGUCAUUGCGAGGGUUCAGGAAGCCCCGGCCUGUGAUCGUGAGCGGAAACCCCUCCUGGAGUUUCCCCAAAGCCAUGGACAGCCCUAGUCUUCGUGAGCUUCAACAGCCUCUGCUGGAGGGCACAGAAUGUGAGACCCCUGCCCAGAAGCCUGGCAGGCAUGAGCUGGGGUCCCCCUUAAGAGAGAUAGCCUUUGCCGAGUCCCUGAGGGGUUUGCAGUUCCUGUCACCGCCUCUUCCCUCCGUGAGCGCUGGCCUGGGGGAACCAAGGCCCCCUGAUGUUGAGGACAUGUCAUCCAGUGACAGUGACUCGGACUGGGAUGGAGGCAGCCGUCUUUCACCAUUUCUACCCCACGACCACCUCGGCUUGGCUGUCUUCUCCAUGCUGUGUUGUUUCUGGCCCGUUGGCAUCGCUGCCUUCUGUCUAGCCCAGAAGACCAACAAGGCUUGGGCCAAGGGGGACAUCCAGGGGGCAGGGGCCGCCUCCCGCCGUGCCUUCCUGCUGGGGGUCCUCGCCGUCGGGCUGGGCGUGUGCACGUAUGCGGCUGCCCUGGUGACCCUGGCUGCCUACCUUGCCUCCCGAGACCCGCCCUAGUUGCCCCUACAGCCCUCACUGUGAACCCUGAGGCCGGCAGCCCAGCAAAUCUGUGGGCAGAGAGUGGAGAAUCUUGGUGGAUGAGGCUGCGGCGGCGGCAGGAGCAUCUAGAAACGGGAGCGAGCUGGACUGGAACCCUUCCCCUUCCUGGCCACCGCUCUUCGGGCGGCAGCAACCUGAGAUUAAACACCAGACACCCUUGCAGCCAAA